AUAGCUGCCAGAAACCACAAAGCAGCAGCAGGGUCAGGAGCAGGGCCGGCAGGACCUGGAUGAUUAGUGGGUUGCUAGUCCAGCCCUCUGGUUGACUUGCCUCCUGUGAUGGACCAGUGUCCUAUGACGGCAGAUGGGUGCUCUCUGAUGAACAAGUGGUCUGUGAUGGACGGGUGCUCUGUGAUAGAUGGGUGGUGUGUGAUUAAUGGGUGCUUUGUGGUGAAUGGGUGGUCUGUGGUGGAUGGGUGGUGUGUGAUGGACGGGUGGUUUGCGGUGAAUGAGUGGUCUAUGAUGGAUGGAUGGUCUAUGAUGGAUGGGUGGUCUGUGGUGGAUGGGUGGUGUGUGAUAGAUGGCUGGUUUUUGGUGGAAGGGUGCUCUGUGAUAGAUGGAUAUUCUGUGGUGAAUGGGUGGACUGUGGUGGAUGGGUGGCCUGUGAUGGAUGGGUGGCCUGUGAUGGAUGGGGGCUCUGUGGUGGGCGAGUGGCCUGUGAUGGAUGGGUGCUCUGUGGUGAAUGGGUGGCCUGUGAUGGAUGGCUGGCCUGUGGUGGAUGGGUGCUCUGUGGUGAAUGGGGGCUCUGUGGUGAAUGGGGGCUCUGUGGUGAAUGGGUGGCCUGUGAUGGAUGGGGGCUCUGUGGCAAAUGGGUGGCCUGUGUUGAAUGGCUGGCCUGUGAUGGAUGGCUGGCCUGUGAUGGAUGGAUGUUCUGUGGUGAAUGGGUGGCCUGUGAUGGAUGGCUGGCCUGUGAUGGAUGGGUGCUCUGUGGUGAACGAUUGGCCUGUGAUGGCUGGCCAGCCUGUGGUGGAUGGGUGCUCUGUGGUGAAUGGGUGGCCUGUGAUGGAUGGGUGUUCUGUGGUGAACGAGUGGCCUGUGAUGGAUGGCUGGCCUGUGGUGGAUGGGUGCUCUGUGGUGAAUGGGGGCUCUGUGGUGAAUGGGUGGCCUGUGAUGAAUGAUUGGCCUAUGAUGGAUGGGGGCUCUGUGGUGAAUGGGUGGCCUAUGAUGGAUGGGGGCUCUGUGGCAAAUGGGUGGCCUGUGUUGAAUGGCUGGCCUGUGAUGGAUGGAUGGCCUAUGAUGGAUGGAUGUUCUGUGGUGAAUGGCUGGCCUGUGAUGGCUGGCUGGCCUGUGAUGGAUGGGUGCUCUGUGGUGAACGAUUGGCCUAUGAUGGCUGGCCAGCCUGUGGUGGAUGGGUGCUCUGUGGUGAAUGGAUGGCCUGUGAUGAAUGGCUGGCCUGUGGUGGAUGGGUACUCAGUGGUGAAUGGCUGGCCUGUGAUGGAUGGGGGCACUGUAAUGGAUGGGUGCUCUGUGGUGAAUGGCUGGCCUGUGAUGAAUGGCUGGCCUGUGGUGGAUGGGUGCUCUGUGGUGAAUGGGUGGCCUGUGAUGAAUGGUUGGCCUGUGGUGGAUGGGUACUCAGUGGUGAAUGGCUGGCCUGUGAUGGAUGGGGGCACUGUAAUGGAUGGGUGCUCUGUGGUGAAUGGCUGGCCUGUGAUGAAUGGCUGGCCUGUGGUGGAUGGGUGCUCUGUGGUGAAUGGGUGGCCUGUGAUGAAUGGCUGGCCUGUGGUGGACGGGUGCUCUGUGGUGAAUGGGUGGCCUGUGAUGAAUGGCUGGCCUGUGAUGGAUGGGUGCUCUGUGGUGAACGACUGGCCUGUGAUGGCUGGCCGGCCUGUGGUGGAUGGGUGCUCUGUGGUGAAUGACUGGCCUGUGAUGAAUGGCUGGCCUGUGGUGGAUGGGUGCUCUGUGGUGAAUGGGUGGCCUAUGAUGAACGGCUGGCCUGUGGUGGAUGGGUGCUCUGUGGUGAAUGGGUGGCCUGUGAUGGAUGGGGGCACUGUAAUGGAUGGGUGCUCUGUGGUGAAUGGCUGGCCUGUGAUGAACGGCUGGCCUGUGGUGGAUGGGUGCUCUGUGGUGAAUGGGUGGCCUGUGAUGGAUGGUUGGCCAGUGACAGAUGGGUGCUCUGUGGUGAAUGGGUGGCCUGUGGUGAAUGGCUGGCCUGUGAUGGAUGGGUGCUCUGUGGUGAAUGGGUGGCCUGUGAUGGACGGGUGUUCUGUGGUGGAUGGUUGCUCUGUGGUGAAUGGGGGCUCUAUGGUGAAAAGGUGACCUAUGGGGAAUGGGUGGCCUGUGGGGAGUGGUUGGCCUGUGGUGGAUGGGUGGCCUGUGAUGGAUGGGUGGCCUGUGAUGAAUGGGUGGCCUGUAGUGGACAGGUAGUCUGUGGUGGAUGCAUGUUCUGUGAUGGAUGGAUGGCCUAUGAUGAAUGGAUGUUUUGUGAUGGAUGGGUGUUCUAUGGUAAAUUGGUGUUCUGUGGCGAAUGGGUGGCCUGUGGUGGAUGACUGUUCUGUGGUGGAUGGGUGCUGUGUGGUGAAUGGGUGGC